GCUUAGCAACCGGGAGGCUUACCUUUGGAAGCUUGUUGCAGCUCUAGCCAAGGUCCUGCCCUCUUCCCGCCCCGCCCCUAGGGUCCAGCUCCCUUCACCUAGGAGCUGCCAAACAUCUGGAUCAACCUGGGCACUACGAGGGGUUGAAUUUCUACCAUUAUCGCGCCUUUUGAUAUUUUUUUCCAGACCUCCUGCUCACAUCCGUAAAGCCCACUGAUUCUUUUACUACACUUUUUAUGAGAACAAGACAUUUUCUAGGAAGAUGGUGGCAGAAAAAGAGACCCUGAGCUUAAACAAAUGCCCAGACAAGAUGCCGAAGAGGACCAAGCUGCUGGCACAACAGCCGCUCCCGGUGCACCAGCCUCACUCUCUGGUUUCUGAGGGUUUCACAGUCAAAGCCAUGAUGAAAAACUCAGUCGUGAGAGGCCCUCCAGCUGCAGGGGCAUUUAAAGAAAGACCAACCAAGCCCACAGCAUUUCGAAAAUUCUAUGAGCGAGGUGACUUCCCAAUUGCCCUUGAGCAUGAUUCGAAAGGAAACAAAAUCGCCUGGAAGGUAGAAAUUGAGAAGCUGGAUUACCAUCAUUAUCUGCCUCUGUUUUUUGAUGGGCUUUGUGAAAUGACAUUUCCCUAUGAGUUUUUUGCUCGGCAAGGAAUCCACGACAUGCUGGAACACGGUGGGAACAAGAUCCUACCUGUCCUUCCACAGCUCAUUAUCCCGAUAAAAAAUGCCUUGAACCUCCGAAACCGACAGGUCAUCUGUGUCACUCUCAAGGUCCUCCAGCAUCUGGUUGUGUCAGCUGAGAUGGUGGGCAAGGCCUUGGUGCCUUAUUACCGUCAAAUCCUCCCUGUCCUGAACAUCUUUAAGAAUAUGAAUGACAUGUGGGAAGUGACCCUUGCAUAGAGACUCGGAAAAACUCUGAAAACAGAACACAUAAAGCUUUAGGAUAUUUUCAAUGACCCAUUCCUGUUCUUUCCUUUACUUGAAAAAGUUCAGAAAGUCCAGGUCUAGGUCACAUUCUAAGAGAGCUCACCCAGAGUGGACUCUGCUUAACCAAAGCCUUCAAGGGGCUCUUUCAGGCAUGAGCAGGAAAAUACAUCCACAAGAGUCCCCGCUGCAUGCAGAUCCCAGGGCCAUCUGCUGUGCUCUCAGAGAUGCUCAUUGUUGUCAUUUAACUGCGAGGGCCACAGAGGGGACAACUGCAGAUUCCUGCUCUACAGCUAGACUCCUGGGGCCCAAUACAGGCCACAGCUCUUCGCAGCCAUGAGAUAUGCGAGCACGCUGCCUAACUCAUCUGUACCACCAUGUUCUCGUCUGUGAAACUUGGGUAUUAACAGUACUUACCUCAUGGGUUUGUUUCAAGGAUUGAGUCAAUAUUAGCAAAGCAUUCAGGACACCACCUGGCACCCAGUGAGUGUGACGUAAAUAGUAAAGAAAUUGGCUUUUCCUGGCACGAUGAUCAAGUGAUUGGUGCCCAGCAGCUCUAAGCAAACUGUCUUUGAAGGGAGAGAAGAAGCCCCAGCAGAGAUUGUUCAGAACAGCUCAACGUCAUGCAGGAGUUGCUCAGCUACACCCAUCUCGGGAUGAUGGAGACUCCAAGUGUUACGUAUUUUGCAAGCUUCAUAAAUCUGACCAGAUAUAGACAGGAGAUUGUAACCUGUGCUUUUUGUUUAUGAAUCUUGUAUUGAGUUGUUGAAGAUGGUUAGGACAAUUUAAUGUUGCAUAAAAACCACUUCUUGUAACAUCUUAAUAGUGAGAAUAGGAGGGUCAAGGCAAGAAAAGUGCUGAGAAAACAAUCCCCCCAAAAAGUUUCUCUCUUAAUUUCAACAUCAUUUUAUGUAUUUUUGUUGUUGUUGUUGUUGGUUUGUUUUAUAGCUUUAAAUGUUAGGAUUACAUUUUGGGGCUUAUUAUUCAAAUCAAAUAUCUGGCACCAUUCAUUUUCUGCUUCCACAUUUGAAAGACCAAAUGUUCAUCAUUUCUGGUGUCGGUUCAGCCUCUGGCCUCCUUUCUAAGACACAUUUUGUAGAGUAUUAGUUUUCCCAUUCAUAGCACGAGAAAAAUAAUACAUUCCUUUUUUAUAAUAGAAAUGUGAUUUGAGGUUGCUUACAGAGUAGGUAGAGGUUUAGGGGGAAAGGCUGUGUUUUGUGUGGCUCUAGGAUGAAUUAUAUGAAAUAAGAUAAGAGGGAAAGCUAUAGUGGGUCACUUGAAUACUGACCUAGUAUUCAACUGUUUUUGAAAAGAAGUUCUGCUCUGCUGUAACUCCUGCUGGCCUUCCAGAAGCAUCAGCUGUGUCACACCACAAGUCUUAAAGGAUCUCCCUUGUUUCCACUGCACAUCUGCCCCCAUGAAUAAACUAAGUGGGCAACAUGGUCAUGGUUAUGUGUUCUUAGCUACUCUGUCCUCAGUGUGUGAAAUGCCCACCUUUAGGGGCGCUGUUGGGGUGAGGCAUUUUAGCUCCCAAAGGAUCCUAUUAGAGUUUGAAGGCCCUGAGACCAGACAGCCACACUGCACAGAGGGGCAGCCUGGACCCACGGGACAUGAGAUGAGUUAAUCCACAGUUAGCCAAGAGGUUACCGCAGAGGUAGAUAUUCACUUAUUCAAAAUUUAAGUGCCUACUAUGUGCAAGGCAGAAAUCUGCGUCUACUUUCUCCUCAUCAGCAAAAGUAGUUCUACUUUUGUUUUUGGUUUUUCUUUUUAAGAAAAAAAAAAUACUGUGGACUUCUGUAUAAUACUCAUUUUAGCCAAAGAAUUCUGCAACUGAAGAGUUUGAGUCAGUCUCCAUGGCAUCCCUGGAUGAGUUCUGGUCAUGAAGGAGCUCAAAUGAUCCUUGUCAGCCGGGGGAAUAAGCUAGACCCAGGCCCUCCCAUGCCUGGCCUCAUUCCUUUUUCAAGGGAACAAUGCCAUACCUCACUAGACCCUAGCUAUACAUUCCUCCAGCCAAAUGCCAGGAAGCAUCUGACCAUGAGACUUUAAGAGCAAAAUGUUGCUUAAAGAAAAAAAUGGGAGCUGUUCUAAAUUCAAGAGCUAAUAGAUAUACUCUUCCAUUUUCUAUGGUCAAAGUCAUAACAUAACAACAUCACUACAAAUUUAAGAAAUAGCUACAGUUAAUUCAGUAGAUAUUGUAGUGAAUGAAUGCCUGAAAUAUGGUUUGAGGGUCACAUAUUUAACCUCAUCAAACCUCAAUUUAUUCAUCAAAAAAUAGAAGUGAUCAUUAUUUUGUUGUGAAGAACAAAUAUUAUAAAGGACCUUAUAAACCAUAAAGCAUUAUACAUAGUUUAUCCUUCUCUUUUCCAUUCCUUAAGCAGGACUGUCAGUGCAAUUGCCUUAUAUUUUAGUGCUAUGGAGUACCCUUAUCUUUUUGCUAAAUAUUACAAAUCCUUUUGCUUACAAAUUAGUCUGUCACUUCUAUUCGAUGGAUUAUCUGUCUACCUCGGGGCUUCUGUGAUGCACAGAGUCAUGGGCUCACUCUCUUUGGCUCAUCUUGUAGGUUUGCAAUCACUCUUACAACUGUCACUUCCAGCCGAUCCAGGACUGCUGCGGCCUCUCUGCUCUGAAAUACACCUAGUAUGUGAAUUUCACAUCACUUCUCAGUCAUAAAACAGACCCAUCAGAAGCUCAUUUUCCUAAGUUUAUUUUAAAUUUAUAGAGCAUUCAUUUCAUCCUUCUCGGUAAUCUUUUUUUUUUUUUUUUUUUUGAGACAGAGUCUCCGUCUGUCACCCAAGCUGGAGUGCAGUGGCACGAUCUCAGCUCACUGCAAGCUCCGCCUCCUGGGUUCACACCAUUCUGCCUCAGCCUCCCGAGUAGCUGGGACCACAGGUACCCGCCACCAUGCCUGGCUAAUUUUUUGUAUUUUUAGUAGACACGGGGUUUCACCAUGUUAGCCAGGAUGGUCUCAAUCUCCUAACCUUGUGAUCUGCCUGCCUCGGCCUCCCAAAGUGCUGGGAUUACAGGUGUGAGCCACCACGCCUGGCCGGUGAUCUUUUUCUCUUUCUCUUUUUUCUUUUCACUUGCUGCUAUUCUAUACAUGCGGAGGAGUUUUUGGAAGGAAAAGAGGGCGCCUUAUUAAUGGUCAUUUUCUACUAAUGGUGAUUUUGAUACUAUUAGAUACCUACUAUGGGCAUUGAAAUUGGUCUCUAGUUCCAUUGAGAAGAGUAGAAAAAUUUCUAGUAUAAGUACAUUCAUAAUGUUUAGAUAAUAUCUUGAGAAAAAAAUAGACAAAUUCACAAGUUCUUCUUUGACUUGAUAGAUUUCUGAGUUCUCAUGUGUUUGUCCAUCUUCAUUCUGCUUUAACGCAUUUACACACACACACACACACUUCCUUUUCUAUUUGUUCAGCUUUACUGAGAUGUAAUUGUGCUAUAGUUGGUUUGUGUGACCCCUCCGAAUCGCUUGUUGAAAUUUGAUCCCCACUGUUAGAGGUGGAGCCUACCGGGCGGUGUUUGGGUGGUACAGGCAGAUCCCUCGCGAAUGGCUUGGUGCCCUGCCCAUGGUAAUGGGUGAGUUCUCACCCUGCUGUUCCCACAAGAGCUGUUUGUUUAAAAAAGCCUGGCACCUCCCCCUCGCUCUCUCGCUUCCUCUCUUGCCACAUGAUCCCUUCGCAACAGCUCCCCUUCGACUUCCACUGUGACCAGAUGCAGCCCCAGAAGUAGACACUGGUGCCACGCUUCCUGUGUAGCCUGCAGAAUCGGAAGACAAAAAACCCCUUUCCUUCAUAAAUUACCCAACCCCAGGUAUUAUUUUAUAGCAACACAAGUGGACUAAGACAAAUUGGUAUAUGAAAACCACACAUAAUUAAUGUGUACAAUUUGGUGAGUUUGGAGGUAUACAUACAUUUAUGUUACCAUCACCACAACAAGGAGACAGACACAUCCAUCAUCUCCAGAAGUUUCCUUUUGCGUGUCUGUGUGAGGGAAGAAAACUUAACAUAAGACUACUGAUACAGCUCCGAAGACUGGAGAAACACCAGGGUCCUUUGUCUCAUGCCAAUGCUAUUAACGACAAGGACACCCGUGGAGUGGUUUUAAGGAGCGGAGAGUUUAACAGGCAAGAAACAAGAAAGAAGAAAACAGCUCCCCGGUACAGAAGGAGCUGGGCUCCUAACGGAGAAAAACCCCGUGUGCCCAGGAAAAACAGUUGUUUAUACCUGGAGGCUGGAGGAGGCGGUGUCUGAUUUGCUUAGGGCCCAGGGGAUUGGCUUGACCAGGUGUGUCAUUCACAUAGCCAACCUGGUCCUCCCACCCUAGCCUUUUAAUAUGCAAAUGCGGGUCGGCAUGAUGUCCUGCACACGUGGUGUUAUUUGGAGGCAGCCAUGACAGCUGUGGUGACAAGGAGAAGAGGGCGGGAACCGCCAUGUCGGGUGGACCUGGUUUUUAGCUGCUGGCAUUUACAUAUCAAUGUUGCCAGCCUGGUUUUUCAAGCUGCUUUCUGUUAGAAAGGAAAUGGUUUGGGGGGUCGCUUUUUAUUAUAGGAAAAUUCCACCAAGAACUCUCACCCUUUCUAGCUGCCUAAAAAUUAUUUCUUAAUAACUCCUAUAUUACUACCCUCCUAACAGAAUUUUAAGUGCACAAUACCUUAUCGUUAACUCUAGGCACCGUGUUGUACAGGAGAUCUCUGGAACUUAUCUUGUGUAACUGUAAUUUGAUAAUCCAUUGAACAGCAACUCUGCAUAUGCCCCCUCUCCAUCCGCUAGUAACCAGCGUUCUAUUGUCUACUUCUGUACAUCUGACUAUUUUUAGAUGCUCCAUAUAAGAGGAAUCACUCAGUAUUUCUUCUUCUCUGACUAUUUCACCUAGCAUAAUGUCUUCCAGAUCUGUCCGUGUUGUCACAAAUGGUAGUAUUUCCUUCUUUUUAAAGCCAGGAUAGUAUUCUACUAUAUGCAUAUACCACAUUUCAUUCAUCAGUGGACAAUUGGGUUGCUUGCACAUCUUGGCCACUGUGAAGGAUGCUGCAGGGAACAUGGGAGUGCAGAUGUUUCUUCGAGAUCACAAUUUCAGUUCUUUUGGGUAUAUACCCAGCAGUAAGAUUGCCUGCUUAUAUGGUAUUCUAUUUUAAUUUUUUGAGGAACCUCCAUGCUGCUUUCCAUAGUGGCAGCAGUAUGUAUUCUUUGGAGAAAUGUCUAUUCAAGUCCUUUGCAUGUUGUAAUUGUGUUUUUUGGGAGUUUUCACUAGUGAGUUGUAGGAGCUCUUUGUAUAUUUCAGAAAUUAACUCCUUAUCACAUACAUGGUUUGCAAAUAUGUUCUCCCAUUGCAUAGGUGGCCUUUCCACUCUGUUGAUUGUUUCCUUUGCUGUGCAGAAAUUGAUGCUGGGGGAAAAAGGGGAUUUGAAGUAUAGGCCAACUUCAGAACAAUUUGACCAGGACUUGCUAAGUUUUUUUUUAAAUUAGGAAAAUACAUAGAAUGUGACUUAAAAAAAUAAUCAAUUACCUAAGACCUUGUCUACUGGGUCUUAAGUUGAAUUUCUAAAUUCUGGAGCCAACUAUGUGACCUUGGGCACGUGAACAAAAGUUAAUUCUAUAAACUAGUUUAAAUCCUGUAGGAAUAUAACAUUAUUUUAUUUUAUUUUAUU